GCCCCAGCUGUGGUGAUGGGUAGCUAGGAGGCCUGGGCCUCUCUGCCUGCUGUAGCCGUCUGCCGCGCCCUUGUUCCUGCAGCUGGCGGAGGAAACAGAGGUUCAGUGAAUUGCCUAGGGUAACACAGGGAAUUGGUGGAAGAGCCAAGUCUAAUGCCCAGAUUUCCAAACUGGGAGUCUUAACCCUUCAUCAGUGCUACCUGUGCCACAUGGGAGAAGAUGGGCCACCUCCAAUUCAUUUUCUCUGGGAACUGCAGGAACCACAAUGAGGUUGCAGAAUGUGUUAACAGUGAAAGCCCUCACAGGACUCAGGUCCAGUUAUCUUUUGACUGCCACAUAUGGACCCCAAAAGAUCUCAAAAGGAAAGUGUCCUCAUUACAGGAGGAAGUGGCUAUUUUGGUUUUCGCCUGGGCUGUGCCCUGAACCAAAAUGGAGUCCAUGUGAUUCUGUUUGACAUCAGCAGCCCUGCUCAAACCAUUCCAGAAGGAAUCAAGUUUAUACAAGGAGACAUCCGCCACCUGUCUGACGUAGAGAAAGCCUUCCAGGAUGCAGACGUCACUUGUGUGUUCCAUAUUGCCUCUUAUGGUAUGUCAGGGCGGGAGCAACUCAAUCGAAACCUGAUCAAAGAAGUCAACGUCAGGGGCACAGACAACAUCCUCCAGGUUUGCCAAAGGAGAAGGGUGCCCAGGUUAGUUUACACCAGCACUUUCAAUGUCAUCUUUGGAGGUCAAGUUAUCAGAAAUGGGGAUGAAUCUCUGCCCUACCUGCCUCUUCACCUCCACCCUGAUCACUACUCUCGGACAAAGUCAAUUGCAGAGCAGAAGGUGCUGGAGGCGAAUGCUACACCCCUGGACAGAGGCGACGGUGUCUUAAGAACCUGCGCUCUGAGGCCAGCUGGCAUCUAUGGGCCUGGAGAACAAAGACACCUUCCCAGGAUAGUCAGCUACAUCGAGAAGGGUCUGUUCAAGUUUGUCUACGGGGACCCCAGGAGCCUGGUUGAGUUUGUCCACGUGGAUAACUUGGUGCAGGCUCACAUUCUGGCCUCAGAAGCCCUGAGAGCUGACAAGGGCCAUAUUGCCUCUGGGCAGCCCUACUUCAUCUCAGAUGGCAGACCCGUGAACAACUUUGAGUUCUUCCGGCCUCUGGUUGAGGGCCUGGGCUACACAUUCCCGUCUACCCGCCUGCCAUUGACCUUGGUCUACUGCUUUGCUUUUCUAACAGAGAUGGUUCACUUCAUUUUGGGUCGACUCUACAACUUCCAGCCCUUCCUCACUCGCACUGAAGUUUACAAAACUGGUGUCACACAUUAUUUUAGCUUAGAGAAAGCCAAGAAAGAGCUAGGUUAUAAGGCUCAGCCAUUUGACCUCCAGGAAGCAGUGGAAUGGUUUAAAGCCCAUGGUCAUGGCAGAAGUUCUGGAAGUCGUGACUCGGAGUGUUUUGUUUGGGAUGGGCUAUUGGUCUUCCUCCUGAUUAUAGCAGUUCUCAUGUGGCUGCCUUCUUCUGUGAUUCUGUCACUGUGAAGGAGGGGCCAGAAAUAAGGUGAUCACAGUUGGCUGAGAUGGUUCUCAAGAAACAUGGGUUUUAAAAUGUGUACAGUGAUAUCUGGUGCCAAACAUUGGCUCUUCAAAUUGCUACUUAAGAAUAGGUUCUUGGAUUGAAUCUUUAUGUCUUAUUUCCUUGCACUAAUCCAGAUGGGAAUGAAAAAGCAGAAGCAGAGAUUAGUUUGAAAUUUGAUUUGUUAUGUGCUUCUGUUUUAGGUGGGUACAAUAGAAGUCAGUUUGGAGCCAUAGAAGUAGGCUUAGUUGAGUUGGAGAUGCCCAUCUUGAAUUUCUGAGAGGGCAAGAUAUACUUAUUUCCAUUUUAUGCAGUCUGCAUCUACCUAAAACCUCUGACUGAUGUGGGAAUGGCGAAACACUAUCAGGCUUGAAUGCGUGUGAAAAACACCAAAUUGGCCCAGAUCCCUAACAGAGCAAUCCUCGAGGGGAUGGUGGCUAUUGCUGGAGAGGCAUUAGCUAUUCACAGGGUACGUUUUAGGUGUUAACUUUUGCCCUUUAUGAUAUCAGGGCAUUAUGCCUAUGUGAACACAUGGUAAUGUUUGAUGUUUAGGCCUUUAUUCUACCUCAUAGGAUUCUUUUGAGGAUUAAAUUCAAGCAUACAAAGCGCUCCUCAACACACAUAGCCAUUCUUUUUAUCAGAAUUGUCAUGGUACAUUCCUUAUGAGGGCUUUCUUCCUCAGUGUUCUCUUUAGAGGGCUAUUGCUACUGGACUUUCUGCAAUGUCUUUGGGUGUGCCCUCAGAGCCUGCAACAAGUGUAUUUGGAUAUACUCUAUUUGUAAAGUUUAGGCCUCUAAGAAGGCCACAAUGAAGCAACUAAAAAUCUGAUGAUUAAGGGAGUCAAUCAAGCUGAUGCCAUUUUUAGUUUAAAAAUGAAGCAGAGCUCUAAACUCAUAGAUGGGUUUUCUUACUGGGAAGAAGAUUGGCUCUCUGAAGACAGCUUCCAAUGAGGAAUGUAUUGAACAAUGGCAGCACUGUCUGGCCACCCACAAACUGUUACAGAUGAUCCAGUUACACUGUUGCAUAGGAACCCAAGUGGAAAGAAGACAGAGUCCAUGUCUGUCCAUGGCUCCAGCUACAGAAAGGAUAGUAUGGGAACAUUACAAGGGGGAUACAUUACUGUGGAAAGUUCUGCUAGAGUUAGUCUUGAGAGUAUCUGUAAAAUACAAAUAGAUGAGCAAUCCCUGUGGAAUGCUGCCUGGAUAUUUUCAGAAAAGCUCUGAACUUGAUGUCAUAAUACCAACACCGUGAAUAUCGUGUGUGGCCUUAACCAAGGAACAGAAGCCCUUUAGAACUUAGCUUCCUCACUUGGGAGCUGGGACUGACUGCAUUUGCCCUUUGUAUAAACCCACCCACCCCAUAGGGUUCACUGGGAGCAUAAAGCAAGAUGUGGUGAAAGUACUUCUAAUAUAAAUUGCAACAUCAGUAUGAGGUGAUGGUAGUGAUUGUUUUUAGGAAAACGUGUUUGGAGUCUUUUCUGUCAUAAAGAAGCUUUUGCAUUAGCCUGGGGUUAACGCAUAUGAGCACCUGCCAUGUAUUGUUCUAGAACUGCUUGAAUAUCCUCAUCCCCAGAGCAGGUCAUCCAAGACAGCAGGGUGGAAGCUGCAUUGUCCUUUAUGACUUGGCCUCAAAUGUCACAGUGUCAUUCCACAGUAUAUUGGUUAUGCAGGUCAAUCCUAUUCAGUAGGGGAAGGAAAUACACAAAGGUAUUUCCGUAUUAUACCAGAAGAGGGAGAUGGUCAAAGGCGAUCUUGGAGGCUGAGCUCUUGGCCCGAUGUGAGUCAUCCUUCCUUUUCCAUGAAACGUUGCCCACAUUUCCAGCUACAAAGCUUUUUCUGCCUGCUUCUUGCCAGAAGGAUUUUAGGGGCCCAACGGCUGUGUUAACAUUUUGCACUAUAUCCCUUUCCAUUCAAGCUGGCAGUGGUACUGGGAACAUUAUUUUGAAUGCGUCACCUGAGUCUUAUUGCAGUUCACUCACAAAAGCCACACCCACAAAUCUCUGAGGUAAGUUCUCCACUGUGAGCUUCUGCUCAGACUGCCAAGGGACAAUACGCUGUGCUUCUUAGAAGCCUUACUGUCUGAACAGCUCUCUGGGGUGCCACAUCAGGCCUUUCUGAGAUCUUAAAAAGAUUUUAUACUCACAGCCACAGCCAUGCACUGUCGUUUCCACAGUCUCGGGUGUUUACACAGGUUAGCCGUAUUCAGUGUGGGAGGAGACUACACAAGGAUAUGAAUACCAGGAGGUGGUGUCAUUGGAGGCCAACGUGGAACCUGGCUACCACAUUCCUGCUUCCAUAUCUCCCCAAUUCUGUUACUGUCUCCCACUCCAGCUUGAAAUGGUAGAUUUUCUCAGUGCUCAUUCCUUGGCCCUGUUCUAAUACCAUACUUUCUCCCUAGGUGAGCUCACCUAAGCCCAUGGCCUCCAUUUUCAUCUCCCAGCCCAAAUAUGUACUACUAGAUGUACAGUUCCAGACCACUCCUGGGCUCCAGACUCAUAUCUAAGUACUUCUGCAACUCCACAUGGAUGUCCCACAUGCACCUGUCAGCCAGUGUAGCCAAAGUGGAAUUCAUAAUCCUCUCCCACCCCAAAUUCUUACAGGGCUCCCUUCCUUAGUAAAUAUCUCCACUACCUGCUGAAUUUCCCAUCCCAGAGAUCUGGGAUAAUCCCUGACCCCUGCCCUCUCCCAGACUUGACACACCUAACCCAUGUUUAAGCCAGUUGAUUUUUACUUGUAAUCAUGCCUUAAAACUGCCCAAGGUAUAGGUGUACCUUCUCUCCCAUAGAUUCCACUAGUAGCCCAUUUGCUCUUCCACCCAUAUCCACACCCUCCUUCCUUCAGUCCAUUCUCCACAUGCCUAGCCAAGAGACUCUAUAAAGGUGCAAAUCUUUUGUCACUUCUCUGCUGAAAACUUUCCUUAGGUUGAGAAUCUUUAACGUGAUCAAGAGGCUUUGUCUGAACUGGCCCCUUGCCUGUCUCUCUAACUUCAUCUCACAUUAUUCUGCCUUCUCUGCCCCAAUUACACUGACCUUUUUUAGGUUCCUGGGCUCCAAGCUUCUCAGGCUCCCUGCUCCUCCUUUUGGCCUGAAUAAUGUUUAUUUCGUGUCUCUUGUUAAGUCUCUUUCUAGAGGCCUUCACUGAUCCCAGCAAUUUAAGAUUGGUGCUCCUGCUACAAAUGAUGCUACAGGCCUGUCAUAGCUUCCUGCCUUUCUUUUAUAGCAUUGCUCAUAACUGUAAACAUUUGUACGGUUAUUUGUUUAAUGCCUGUUAGCUCUAUGAGGGUGGGAACUUUGUCUUGCUUACAGCUGUACUCCUAAUGCCCGGCACAGUGCAGGAGUUCAAUAAGUAUUUGUCCAAUGAAUGCUGUUUUCCCAUCUGCUAUGGAUGAACACUCUUUUCUAGCACACAGAUAACUCACUGUUUCUAAUCUUUUGGAGACUGGGGAAAAUAGCCAACCUACACUAGAACUGUCGUAACUAAGUCAAGAUUAGAUGAGGUCUAGUGAGUAAGGGAAGUCAUUGUCUAUAUGAUCUGGUGGAGUAUUAAUGCUAUAAGGAGGUCAGGGAAUGGGGAAGGAAUGUGGGCCAAGUGAUUUGUGCUCCCUCCACAUCUCAGCUGAAAACUCACCACUUUAAAAGACUUAGUCUAUUUCCUGAAAGGGAGCUCCCCUUCCUUUCUAUGGUCAGGAGACGCUGCAGUUAAGAAAUUCUAUUAGUUCUAGGGUUCCCAGCUGCCCUCACCUUGCCUCAACCUUAGAUUGAAUCACUCAACCCUGCCUAACAAUAAAAUUAUGCUCACACUUGUGCACUUGGGGAUGCUCUCAGAGGUCUGGGCAGAAGCCACCCAGCACUGCUACCUCACCCAUGGCUUCUGAGGAGUGUGUGGGAGGUUAUCCAUAUGAUUGAUGGAGGGUCGCAAUGAAGGAAGGAUGUGUGAGCAACAAGGAGCCCUGUAUUGGAACCUAAAGGUAAUGCCCAAACUGCUCCCACCUGCAAAAAGGGAAGAGCGGUCUGGAAAGCCUGUUGGAAAUACUUCUUGGAUGUCCUCAGUGCCGUUUCUGGUGACAGGGGCAGACAGUGCCACAUUACAAGCAGUAACAGUUAGUGGAGGGUCAAAUAACUCAUUCUGGCACCAAAUUACCUAUGCUGUGGUGUUUCUCAAACCUAGGGAAUAGGCCUAGGGAUUCUUUUCAAGAAAAUGUUUUAUUUUCCUCAACCAUCUAACAUGGUGUAUAAAAGAGGCAAGUGUUGCUUUGUCGUAGAUUGUUGGGGCUGCUUCUACCUUGUAUUGCUUUCCAAAUCUCCGGUUCGCCCAGCCUUACAAAGGGUAGAAGUUGCCUGCAGAAUGCCACGCCCCAGCUCUGACCCAAUUAGACAUCAUUAUAGGGCCACUGGUGCCCCUGCUGGCUGGCCUUGGAAGCCAGCACCAGCAAUGUUAUUAAAAUCUUCACCAGCAUCUCUUGCUUAGAGAUGGCACACCAGGUUGUGUGCUGUUCACCAGCAUAUCUCACUUUAGAGAAUGAUACCCCAUGCUCCUUUUUGGUGACAAAAAGUCCCUCCCAGCCCUUUCGUGGGGCUGACCUCCACAUGCAGGCCUGACCGCUCACAGGACUUCCAUCCUUCGGCCGCAGUCAUUGGGCCACGAUGGGCCAGUCAGCGUCAUCCUUUCAGCCUUUCUCCCAGAGCAGGUUUAGAGAAACCCUUUCAGCUAGGAUUGCUUCUCUGGGGAGGACAGGCGCUUGGUGCAGCUCCUCUUCAGGGUCCUCCUACCUGAAGGAGAGGACCGAGUGCUGAUGAUGUUUGGGCUGCUGGGUCCAGCUAUGUGUUAAGAAGAGCCAAAAAAUGGAGAGGGAGGAGGUCCUGGUGACUACACUGGGGUUCCGUAACGCUGCCUGCGGGACGCUCAUCAUUCCAGAUCGUCCUCUCACGUGAGUCUUCAGUUCACUUUCUUUUCUGCUUAAGGUCCUUUAAGUUCGAUUUUUCUCCAGGAAUCGCAGCAUGUCCUGGUGUGCCAUGUCCACAGUCCACUCCUGGGUACAGGUGAUCCUACCCCGUGGUUUCCAAAGGCAGCCUCUCCACUCACCUCUGUGCCCUCUUUCUUUCAAACGGGGGUCGUCUUUUGGUCCCUGGGUAAUUUAACAUUUGCUGGAGUUUUUCUUAAAAAAUGAGAUUGAUUUCCUUUUCUAGAAUCAUGUUUAUUUGAAUUACGUUUAUUCAAAUCAUGUAUAUUUGGCACCAACAUACCUUUAAGCAGAGUAGUUCAAACUCUUGUUUUAUAUGGAAAUUGUUUGAUGAAGUGAUUUGCUCCCCAGAACAUAAACGCCCCAUGAGAGCAGGAACCAUGUCUGUUUUUUCUACUUCUGUACCCUUCAUAUGCCCAAUAAAUGCUUGUUGACGGGGUGAAUGCACUUAUCAGCCAGGUGGUCCCUUAUCUGAAAUUACAGCUGAUUCCCCAGUUAUUGCUUCUUUUACACCUGAGACUCCCAGCCUGAGGCAAUAAGAACAUUCAAGGCCUAAAUUAAAAAUGCAGACUCCAGAAGGGUGACAUCAUGUAAAACGGCAGAGUAGGAAGCUCUGGAAUCGGUCCUUUCACUGUAACAACCAGAAAAGCACGGGGGCAGGGGAAUGAUCAGAACCAAUGAUUUCAGGAACUCCUUACAUCUAUUUUACCUCGAUAUACAGACUCCAGACUCUUCCCUGAUGCUUCUGAUUGAGAAAGUCUGUGUUGGUUGGUAAUCUGCACUCUAGGUGUUUCUUAUCUUUCAACAAGGAGGUGAGCACUGGUGCCAGAUACUAAACACUGGCUCCCUUGCAAGAUGCUGAGAGGCUCCUGACUUCUGCUUGGCUCUUCCCUUUGCAGUGCUUUGCUACAGCAGGUGCUCAGUACAACUUUGCUGAAUGAAUGAAGGGGGAGAUGGGACUCGCCAAAGGGCCUUGGAUUCGAGUGACCCCCCACCUGCUCCUUUAUGCAGGGCCCAGUUCUUUGUUGACACAGACAAGCACUGCUACGUCCCAGUGCUGACUUUUCCAGCCAACCUAGAGCCUCUUUUUCUUGAGCCAAAGGGAUUCUUUGGCAACACAUCUUGUUGUGCCUGGUUACCUGAUCUUUUAGUGUAAAACAGCCUUUUGCUAUUGAAAAUCAAACCAGAAAUAGAGUCAACCAGUCCCUGGUAUCUCUAAGUUGUGCAAAUUCAUACCAUGUUACCCUUCUGUAUUUUAGAACCUGGGCACACCAGGAACUCAUUGAACUCAAGUUGCGUUCAUAAUUACUUGAGUUCAUUGAACUCAAGUAAUUAUGACCGAGGCCAAAUCUAGUUCACUACAAAGAAAUUGCAUGUAGCAAAGUGAUCCAGGCAAGUGUCUUUCAACCAACAGGGGAUUUAUCAGCAGUAAUUCGCAAUGUUUAUUUUUAACAGCUGGUUAAAGCAUGCAAGUAAUUAAAAAAUUCUUCAUUACUAAUAUGCAAGAUUUUAAUCUUGGCAAGUAUUCUACAUAUCUUUUGCUCUAGCCUCCCAGUGGAGCCAUAUUUCAGAUCCAAGAGUAAAAUACUGUCUUACCCAUAUAUAUAUUUUAACAUAUGUAUAUAUGUUAUAAGAAUGAGUCGUCUUUUGCUCUUAACAGUCACUAGGAGUUAGUGUCCUGAAUAGAUAAUAAUAAGUCUGAAAUGUUGCCCAGGUUUUAAGGGGAAUUAUUUGCACAUUGCUGGGCAAUUACAACACCCCCACUCCACUGAUUUAUAGUCCUGUGCCUUUCAUAGGGGAUUUAGCUUCUGGGAAUGUUCAACAUGAAGCUAAUGAUCAAUAUUAACCUGUCACCCUAGUUAACUAAAUUACUCAAAGAUGAACAUUGUUAAUAGUUAAUUGCUACUAUUUGUUGAGAGUUUACUCAGGAUAAGGCUUUCUAAUUUUUUUUUCUUUUUUUUGAGAUGGAGUUUUGCUCUUGUUGCCCAGGCUGGAGUGCAAUGGCGUGAUCUCAGCUCACUGCAACCUCCACCUCCUGGGUUCAAGCGAUUCUUCUGCCUCAGCCUCCUGAGUCAAUAGGAUUACAGGCGCCCACCACCACAACCGGCUAAUUUUUGUUUAAUUAGCGGUGAUUUGGGGUUUCGCCAUGUUGGCCAGGCUGGUCUCAAACUCCUGACUUCAGGUGAUCCACCUGAGGCUUUCUUUAUUUCUUAGGCUUAUUUAGCUUUCUUAAUGUCUUUAAGAAACAGAUCAAUUUAUUAUCUCCAGUUUACAUGGGAGGAAACUGAGGCUUAGGGAGAUGCAGUACCUUGCCCAAGGGUACCCAGCGUCACCAGCUAGGAAGUGGCAAAACUUAAAUUUGAGCCAGGUUUACUUGAAUCCAAGACCAAAUUUUUUUUUUUUUUUUUUUGAUAGAGUCUCGUCUGUCACCCAGGCUAGAGUACAGUGGCACAGUCAUGGCUCACUGUUGGCUCGAACUCCUGGGCUCAAAUGAUUGUCCUACCUCAGCCUCCCAAGUAACUGGGACUACAGGUGCAUGCCACCACAUCCAGCUUUUAUUUUCUGUAGAGACGGUGUUUCACUAUGUUACCUGGGCUGGUCUUGAAUUCCUUGCCCCAAGCAAUCCUCUUGCCUCGGCCUCCCAAAGUGCUGGGAUUACAGGUAUGAGCCACCGAGCCUGGCCCAAACUCUUACCUUGUUGGAGGUGGUUUUAUCACGUUAGCAUGACAUUAUUCAAGGCUAAGUGUUACUCGAACUUCAUUUGCAAUUAAAGUAAACUAUUUGUUACAAAAAAUGAGUAACUGUAAAUAGUGACUUCUGCUACACAAACUAAGUUACAGAAGCAAACCAUUAUUUUGUCAUGUGAGUAUGUAUUACGUAGAGCUGAGGUGUGUGGGCGGGGGGUGCUGUUAAUCUACUGGAAUUCCAUGUAUUUUGUGAGGAGCAUGGAUGUUAGAGCCAUACUUAAUAGCCCAGAGGACAUCCUCCAGGAAGACUUGUUUGUGUACCUAAUCAAAUACUGAUAUUGGUCACAUUGCACAUGUCCUAGUCUCUCCUCUAAAUCAGUAUCUUGAGAGCAGAGCCCAAGUAUUAUUCGCUGCUGAUGGCUCUUUGCCUCCCCUGCAGUCUUACACUAUUCUGGGCGUGGAGCACAGACCUAAUAAAAAUCUUUCGAAGUAAUGAAAAUGCAAAGUCCAGCCUGUAGAGGUGCCCUUAGAUGUUUAAAUUCUCCCAAAGAAGGGUGAACUUUUUACAAAGCACUUCACAGUGGAAGUGUCUCUGAGCACAGCAAAUACCUUAAGUUUGGGCCCAAGUGGAAAAGAAAUAUUUGGUAGUGGGUGAUUAUAGCCCUUCAGUGCUCAAGGGACUCAUGCAUUUGCUUGCACUUCCUUAUGCCUGUCCUGGAGCCAUCUCUUAUUUGCAAUGUGACUUUGAGCAAAUGCCUCUCAUCUGUAAAGUGGAGAUAAAACAUUCCCUGCUUAUCUCUUGGGGGAACUUGUAUGGAUUUAAUGGCACAGAGGCCUUUUGUAACCUGUACAAGAACUAUGCACAUGGAUCCUUAAUUAAUAGUGUUUCUGCUGGGAAAGAUGGAAGGGUUUGGAGGGGAAGCUGGUGUCUACAGGAAGAGAUGCAAGACAUGCUAGUGGAGUUUGAGACGUUCAAAUGGAAUGUUCAGUAACUAAUUAGCAACAUAAGACUGUAGUUUGAAAAAAACAACUGCAUAUGCGGGUAGAGAUGGUUCAGUGAAAAUGUUUCAUUGAUUUCCUGCCAUAUAACAGGUAUUAGUUUAUUUACCGUGGCUUUUCUUUUUUUCUUUUGAGACAUGGUGUCACUCUGUCGACCAGGCUGAAGUGUAGCACUGUGGACACAGCUCACUGCUGCAGUGCCCUCCUGGGCUCAGGUGAUCCUCCUAAGUAGCUAGAACCACAGGUGCACCAGCACACCUAGCUAAUUUUUCUGUCGUCUUUUGUAGAGACAGGGUCUCACCGUUUUGCCCAGGCUGGUCUCAAACUCCUGGCCUUAGGUGAUCCUCCUUCCUCAGUCUCCCAAAGUGGUGAGAUUACAGGAAUGAGCCACCGUGCCCAGCCUACCAUGUUUUUUUUGUUUGUUUGUCUGUUUCAGACGGAGUUUUGGUCUUGUGGCCCAGGCUGGAGUGCAGUGGCACAAUCUUGGCUCACUGCAACCUCCGCCUCCCAGGUUCGAGUAAUUCUCCUGCCUCAGCCUCCCAAGUAGGUGGGAUUACAGGUGCCCGCCACCACGCUCAGCUAAUUUUUGUAUUUUUAGUAGAGAUGGGGUUUCACCAUGUCAGCCGUGAUGGUAUCGAACUCCUGAGCUCAGGUGAUCCACCCACCUCGGCCUCCCAAAGUGCUGGGAUUACAGGCUUGAUACCAUGGUUUUCAAUUACUCAAUUCAGUCACGUUUUGAGCUCUAAACUGAAAAUGAGUUUUUCUUUUCUUGAGAUUGCAGAGUCAAUUACACCAUGCUAGAGAACAAGUAGGCAUCUAUGCCUCUCUGCUCUAAAUUUUGAUGUCUAUAAACACCCAUAGCGGUGUGUGUUGGUUUUAAAUUGUGGGGCUAGAAAGCCAACCCAAAAUCAUCAAGCUUUUAUUUCUACACAUUCAGAGUGCUUCUGUGUAACUUAGAUUUAAAAGUAACUAUACAAAUAAUGCAUAGAUGUAUUUUUCUUAUAUAAUGUUAAAAUAUUACGGAUAAGGCCAAAGACCCCUUUUACUAAUGUCCCCAAAUUUCAUAUAUGUAUAUAUUUGUAUAGAAAACAGGGCUGUGGUGUUCAUGUCUUUCCCCAUACUACUGUCUCCCACCUCACAGUUCCUUCUGCUACUACGGUUUCUCACUCAAUAGUACAGCAUGGUGAUCUAUUGAUAUUAGUAUAUAUUCUUUAUUUGCUGACAUAGGAGGUCACCGGGUAUAUAAAGAUGAUAAGCAUAUGUCCUAGUUGGCCUAAGACAGUUCUGGUUUCAUGCCUGUAGUCCCACCUUAAUUUUUAAUAGUGCUUCCUUUCACUCUCAGGUAUGUCCCAUUUUGUAUAAUAAAUUGUACGAUCACCCUAUAUAUAAGACACAUAGUUAUAUGAAGAAUUAAGCAUUUUUCAUAACAGAUGUAUUAGAAGUUAUUGUGAACUGAUUUUGAGGGGAAAAAAUCUCAUUUUGUACUAGAAUAGAAUAUAGUAGAAAAUCCUGAAUUCUGGGUAUGUAGCAGUAUUCUACCAACAUUGAAAUAUUAAUAAAAAAUUACCUAAAGAAAA